CCCCAGGCUGGAAUGCAGUGGCGUGAUCUCGGCUCACUGCAACCUCCGUCUCCUGGGUUCAAGAGAUUCUCCUGCCUCAGCCUCCUGAGUAGCUGGGAUUACAGGUUCCUGCCACCACACUCAGCUAAUUUGUUUGUAUUUUUAGUAGAGAUGGAGUUUCACCAUAUUGGUCAGGCUGGUCUCAAACUCCUGACCUCAGGUGAUCCACCUGCCUUGUCCCAAUUGGAAGCGCACUGCGCGGCCUCCACCGCGCUCUCGGCCCGGGUUCGGCGUGGGGGCGGGGAGGGGGCGGGGCGCCUAUAUUACGUGCGCGGCGCCGCUCCUGCGAGAGGACGUUGCGUGCUCGCUCGCGCCAGGCGAGUCUCCGCGUCUCCCUCGCGAACUCGGUGA